AGUGUGUAAGACGCUCACGGGCGCGCGGACUAUCGGGCGGCUAGGCUCUCUGAGGAGGCUGCCACAGUGAAGCAACCGUGACAAGUGGUGCCCGACCAGGGACCUGAACGAGGAAGGUCUGCCAGAGCAGAGAAAGUGAAACUGAUCAGACGAACUACGAACCCCUGGACGGGAGAGUCUGCCGGCGGAGAAUAUAAGGAGAUGGACAAACCGUGUGGGUGCCCUCCAGGUGUGUGUGACCAUGGAACGGGAGACCGGAGGGAUCCAUGGUAUUCAACCGUGGGCCUGUUACCUCCAGUACGAGCCAUGAGCCAGCGGAAUCUGAAUGCAAAGACAGAACAAGGGCCGACCGGAGUCACAAUGACAUCCAACCCCAUAACAUGGGGACAGAUCAAGAAAACGACACAAGAAGCUGAGAAACUACUGGAGCGCCAGGGUCAGGCAAAAACCCCUGACUCCAUGUUCUUGGCCAUGCUAGCUGUAGUGUCCUGUGCGUCUAUAGGAUCGGGUGAACCACCAACCGGCAAUUGAAAGCUGCACAGCCUGAAAUUACCUUUAUUCAAUUAAUGCAAAAACAAAAGGGGAGAUGUUGGAGGCCGAAGGAAUGAGGGUCGUGACCAACUCAGUAUACCACUGGAGGCUCUGUGAGCAAACAGCAAACUGUUCUCAUGAAAGCAGGAUGUUGGCGAACUGACAAACUCUGUCUGCCGCCAGAAGGAAUGCUGGGGGCAGUCAUGUCCCAGGUCCCGUGCUCCUUGAGGUUAUCCACAGGAACAUCCAGAACCUGUUGAACAAAGAAAGGAAUCAUGUGGGCCUGUGUUAAAUCAAAUAGCUGACCGACAGUUAUCCCUUCCUCCCUAUUCACUCUACCUAAUAAAUAUGAAGGGCUGUAAAAGCUCAGGUCCCUGUUCCCUAAUAUCAAGGAGCCCCCUGACCCCUUCUUUCAAACAGAUCCUUUUGUCUGUCUCAUUUCUGCAUUCGUCGUCCUUCGUUCGGUCCAGAAGCAACCGCGACAGUCCUGCAUGUGUUGAUGCCACCUGUAUGUGCAGGUGUGACCUCAGGUGUGUGAGUAUCCCUCAUACCCCUUAUCAUCACUGCCUAUUCGCUCUUCCUCCAGCCUCUGGCAACCACUAAUCCACGUUAUAUGUCUAGAUUUGCCUCUUCUGGACACUUCAUAUAAAUGGAGUCAUACAAUAUGUGGUUUCUUGUGUCUGGCUUUUUACCACUGAACGUUUUCAGAGUUCAUCCAUGUUGUAGCAUGUAUCAGUUUUUCAUUCCUCUUUAUGGCUGAAUAAUACUGCAUUGUAUGGAUAUACCACAGUUUGUUUACUCAUUAGUUCAUAGACAUUGGGGUUGUUUCCAACUCUCUGAUAUUAUAAAUGCUACUGCUGUGAAAAUUCAUGUACAGGUGUUUGUGUGGAUGUAUAUUUUUAAUUUGGGAAGGGGAGGCCAUGGGUGGGACCUAGGCUUGUGAAGAGCCUGGCCUGGGUGUAUCUGUUUGUCCGAGGAGUGCCUGUAUGCAUGGCCAUGACCACACCCACUCCUUGCUGCCUGUGCUCAUUAGCCAUACUUCAUUUUCCAGAAUCCCAGGCCUGGGCCCCUGAAGUCAAAGCCAGGAGCCUAGAGCCACACUGAUGUGUAGGAUCAAAGAGAAGGCGGCAGUGGCCCUGGAAACAAACCUGUCUCUGCAAGAGUCACUAGCAACCUGGGACCUCUGCCCAGGACUGAGACCUCGGGUGCCCCCUACCCUGUAGCUGCUGAGGCCAAGCAAUGUGGAGACAGAGAGAGGGUGAGGUGAUGGAGCCUGAGGUGCCGAGUGAGGUAGAUGGUGGGGUGGCAGUCACAGUGGCACAGGAGGCAGGUACAGGGCUAGAUGUUUUCAGAAACCAGAUAUCCCUCUAAAACACACCCUGCUUCUGCUGCCUUCAUUCCACUGCCCUGCCUUCCUCAGCCUGCUCUACACCACUACCUCCUCAUGGUUCUCCUGCCUCCCGUUGCCCCCUUCAUCACUCUCCACUCAGCAUUGGGUAGAGAGGGUCUUUUACCCCUGACUGAUGAGGCCACCCCUCUCUUUAAACCCUCCAUCACUGCCCAGGCCAUCAGAGUAUGGUUGGCAAACUCUUCUGUAAAACACAAGCAGCAGGCUGGGCGCAGUGGCUCAUGCCUGUAAUCCCAGCAUUUUGGGAGGCUGAGGCAGGCCUGAGGUUGGGCCUAUGAGACCAGCCUGGCCAACAUGGUGAAACCCUGUCUCUACUAAAAAUACAAAAAAUUAGCUGGGCGUGGUGAUGCAUGCCUGUAAUCCCAGCUACUCGGGAGGCUGAGGCAGGUGAAUCGCUUGUUCCCAGGACAUAGAGAUUGUGGUGAGCCAAGAUCGUGCCUUUGCACUCCAGCCUGGGCAACGAGCGAAACUCUGUCUCAAAAACCAAACAAAAAACACACAAGCAGCAAAUGUCAGCUUUGUAGGCUCAGAGAGAAAACCAAGAAUGUUACAAAGGUACCUAUCUAACAAGAGAAAAACAUGUCCAUACAUUUUAUUAAUAAAAUCCAAAACUUUGUUAAA